ACAUCUCGCGGCGAGGAGGAGAGGCCGGAAGGGCGCCCCAGCCCCAGGGCUCCUGCCCCGCCUGGGCCUCCGGCUUUCGUUUCCCCGCAACGCUUCGCUUUCGUUUCCCGCUGGCGCCUGGCUCCCUCCGGGUUUCGUUUCCCGCCGGCGCCUGGCUCCCGCCAGGUUUCGUUUCCGAGGCGGGGCCGAGGGCGGCGUCGCUGAGGCGCCCAUGGCCUUCGCCCGCCGGCUCCUGCGCGGGCCACUGUCGGGGCCGCUGCUCGGGCGGCGCGGGGUCUGCGCUGGGGCCAUGGCUCCGCCGCGCCGCUUCGUCCUGGAGCUUCCCGACUGCACCCUGGCUCACUUCGCCCUAGGCGCCGACGCCCCCGGCGACGCAGACGCCCCCGACCCCCGCCUGGCGGCGCUGCUGGGGCCCCCGGAGCGCAGCUACUCGCUGUGCGUGCCCGUGACCCCGGACGCCGGCUGCGGGGCCCGGGUCCGGGCGGCGCGGCUGCACCAGCGCCUGCUGCACCAGCUGCGCCGCGGCCCCUUCCAGCGGUGCCAGCUGCUCAGGCUGCUCUGCUACUGCCCGGGCGGCCAGGCCGGCGGCGCACAGCAAGGCUUCCUGCUGCGCGACCCCCUGGAUGACCCUGACACCCGGCAAGCGCUGCUCGAGCUGCUGGGCGCCUGUCAGGAGGCACCACGCCCGCACUUGGGCGAGUUCGAGGCCGACCCGCGCGGCCAGCUGUGGCAGCGCCUCUGGGAGGUGCAAGACGGCAGGCGGCUGCAGGUGGGCUGCGCACAGGUCGUGCCCGUCCCGGAGCCCCCGCUGCACCCGGUGGUGCCAGACUUGCCCAGUUCCGUGGUCUUCCCGGACCGGGAAGCCGCCCGGGCCGUUUUGGAGGAGUGUACCUCCUUUAUUCCUGAAGCCCGGGCAGUGCUUGACCUGGUCGACCAGUGCCCAAAACAGAUCCAGAAAGGAAAGUUCCAGGUUGUUGCCAUCGAAGGACUGGAUGCCACGGGUAAAACCACGGUGACCCAGUCAGUGGCAGAUUCACUUAAGGCUGUCCUCUUAAAGUCACCACCCUCUUGCAUUGGCCAGUGGAGGAAGAUCUUUGAUGAUGAACCAACUAUCAUUAGAAGAGCUUUUUACUCUUUGGGCAAUUAUAUUGUGGCCUCCGAAAUAGCUAAAGAAUCUGCCAAAUCUCCUGUGAUUGUAGACAGGUACUGGCACAGCACGGCCACCUAUGCCAUAGCCACUGAGGUGAGUGGGGGUCUCCAGCACCUGCCCCCAGCCCAUCACCCUGUGUACCAGUGGCCAGAGGACCUGCUCAAACCUGACCUUAUCCUGCUGCUCACUGUGAGUCCUGAGGAGAGGUUGCAGAGGCUGCAGGGCCGGGGCAUGGAGAAGACCAGGGAAGAAGCAGAACUUGAGGCCAACAGUGUGUUUCGUCAAAAGGUAGAAAUGUCCUACCAGCGGAUGGAGAAUCCUGGCUGCCAUGUGGUUGAUGCCAGCCCCUCCAGAGAAAAGGUCCUGCAGACGGUAUUAAGCCUAAUCCAGAAUAGUUUUAGUGAACCGUAGUUACUCUGGCCAGGUGCCACGUCUAACUAGAUUAGAUGUUGUUUGAAACAUCUACAUCCACCAUUUGUUAUGCAGUGUUCCCAAAUUUCUGUUCUACAAGCAUGUUGUGUGGCAGAAAACUGGAGACCAGGCAUCUUAAUUUUACUUCAGCCAUCGUACCCUCUUCUGACUGAUGGACCCGUCAUCACAAAGGUCCCUCUCAUCAUGUUCCAGUGAGAGGCCAGCGAUUGCUUUCUUCCUGGCAUAGUAAACAUUUUCUUGGAACAUAUGUUUCACUUAAUCACUACCAAAUAUCUGGAAGACCUGUCUUACUCAGACAGCACCAGGUGUACAGAAGCAGCAGACAAGAUCUUCCAGAUCAGCAGGGAGACCCCGGAGCCUCUGCUUCUCCUACACUGGCAUGCUGAUGAGAUCGUGACAUGCCCACAUUGGCUUCUUCCACAUCUGGUUGCACUCGUCAUGAUGGGCUCGCUGCAUCUCCCUCAGUCCCAAAUUCUAGAGCCAAGUGUUCCUGCAGAGGCUGUCUAUGUGUCCUGGCUGCCCAAGGACACUCCUGCAGAGCCAUUUUUGGGUAAGGAACACUUACAAAGAAGGCAUUGAUCUUGUGUCUGAGGCUCAGAGCCCUUUUGAUAGGCUUCUGAGUCAUAUAUAAAGACAUUCAAGCCAAGAUGCUCCAACUGCAAAUAUACCAACCUUCUCUGAAUUAUAUUUUGCUUAUUUAUAUUUCUUUUCUUUUUUUCUAAAGUAUGGCUCUGAAUAGAAUGCACAUUUUCCAUUGAACUGGAUGCAUUUCAUUUAGCCAAUCCAGUAAUUUAUUUAUAUUAAUCUAUACAUAAUAUGUUUCCUCAGCAUAGGAGCUAUGAUUCAUUAAUUAAAAGUGGAGUCAAAACGCUAAAUGCAAUGUUUGUUGUGUAUUUUCAUUACACAAACUUAAUUUGUCUUGUUAAAUAAGUACAGUGGAUCUUGGAGUGGGAUUUCUUGGUAAAUUAUCUUGCACUUGAAUGUCUCAUGAUUACAUAUGAAAUCGCUUUGACAUAUCUUUAGACAGAAAAAAGUAGCUGAGUGAGGGGGAAAUUAUAGAGCUGUGUGACUUUAGGGAGUAGGUUGAACCAGGUGAUUACCUAAAAUUCCUUCCAGUUCAAAGGCAGAUAAAUCUGUAAAUUAUUUUAUCCUAUCUACCAUUUCUUAAGAAGACAUUACUCCAAAAUAAUUAAAUUUAAGGCUUUAUCAGGUCUGCAUAUAGAAUCUUAAAUUCUAAUAAAGUUUCAUGUUAAUGUCAUAGGAUUUUUAAAAGAGCUAUAGGUAAUUUCUAUAUAAUAUGUGUAUAUUAAAAUGUAAUUGAUUUCAGUUGAAAGUAUUUUAAAGCUGAUAAAUAGCAUUAGGGUUCUUUGCAAUGUGGUAUCUAGCUGUAUUAUUGGUUUUAUUUACUUUAAACAUUUUGAAAAGCUUAUACUGGCAGCCUAGAAAAACAAACAAUUAAUGUAUCUUUAUGUCCCUGGCACAUGAAUAAACUUUGCUGUGGUUUACUAAUCUA